ACUACCCGGCCUGCCCCGCGGCAAGAUGGCGGCCUGAACGCAGCUGGCAGCGGCGGAAAGUUUGUUGUGGGGUUGGAGUAGUCGGGCGGGGAAGCCAGAGUUGGGGAGGAUUGCGGGGGCCCUAGCCUGUAGUAGGGGCGAAGGGGGUACUGGCUCCAGGGUUGAAAAGAGGAGAUGGAAUGGAGUAAGGUCCGAGGCGGAGAGGAAAAAAAGGAGCUGGGGCGGACCGGGGCCCUAGGGUCCAGUGGCAGCCCUAGGGGAGGGGGAUUUGGGGGCGGGGCAGCCAGAAGUAGGUGUUGUGCAGGCCCUGGAGAAGCAGAGUCACAAGUUGGAGGAAAAUUUCUUAGCCGCGAAUAAAGAAGCCUGGAGCGUGGGAUAGAGGCCCGACUGUAUCUGGCCGGCCAGAGGGGAAAGGGAUCUUUCUAGUAGAGUGGGAUAGUGAGGAAGAGAGAUCUGGAGGAUGCCGGGCAGAUCUGCUAAGGAGGGAACUAAAGCCAGUCAAAUGACCCUCUUCUAGGCUUAGAUCAGCCUUUCCACAGCUGUUAGCAGCAUCUGCCCCAAUUUCAGCUGAAGAUUCAGGUGCCCCAGGGACUGGAAGAAAUUACAGUGCCUACUUGGAAAGAAGAAGAGAUAGCGACUUGCCCCAGUCCAACCCCAGAGCGGGUACCUGCUGUCACUGACUCCUGAAUUCAUUCUCGCUGUGUGUCUACUUUUGCUUUUUUGGAGCUGUGGCUAAAGGAAGUGGAGGGGCCGUGGGAUGCGGAGAGCCGAGGGCUAACUCCCGGACAGCGGAACAGAGAGAGCUGCCGACAAACAGACGUCCAGAGUCCUUCUGGCCACAUCUCUGAGCCUGCCUCCUUCUUGCUUCUCAGCAGGCGGAGGAGCCGUCACCUCCCAGAAUGACUAGUGCCGCCCCUGCUAAGAAACCCUACCGUAAGGCACCACCAGAGCAUCGGGAGCUGCGUUUGGAAAUUCCUGGAUCCCGGCUUGAGCAGGAGGAACCCCUGACUGAUGCAGAAAGGAUGAAGCUCUUACAGGAGGAGAAUGAAGAGCUUCGCCGGCGCCUGGCCUCCGCCACCAGACGCACUGAGGCCCUGGAACGUGAGCUGGAAAUUGGGCAGGACUGCCUGGAGCUGGAGCUGGGCCAGAGCCGCGAGGAGCUGGACAAAUUUAAGGAUAAGUUCCGCAGGCUGCAGAACAGCUACACGGCUUCCCAGCGGACCAACCAGGAGUUGGAGGACAAGCUGCACACACUGGCCUCUCUUAGCCACAGCUGGAUUUUUGCAAUCAAGAAGGCUGAGAUGGAUAGGAAGACGCUGGACUGGGAGAUUGUGGAGCUGACCAACAAGCUGCUGGAUGCCAAGAACACCAUCAACAAGCUGGAAGAGCUCAAUGAGCGGUACCGGCUGGACUGCAACCUGGCUGUACAGCUCCUCAAGUGCAACAAGUCCCACUUCCGAAACCACAAGUUUGCCGAUCUGCCCUGUGAGCUACAGGACAUGGUUCGGAAACAUUUGCACAGUGGUCAAGAGGCCGCCAGCCCAGGUCCUGCUCCCAGCCUAGCCCCAGGGGCUGUGGUGCCUACCUCAGUCAUUGCCCGAGUGUUAGAGAAGCCGGAGUCUCUACUGCUCAAUUCAGCCCAGUCAGGCAGCGCCGGGCGCCCCUUGGCUGAGGAUGUCUUUGUGCAUGUGGACAUGAGUGAGGGUGUCCCAGGUGAUCCAGCCAGUCCCCCGGCCCCUGGCAGCCCCACCCCACAACCCAAUGGGGAGUGCCACUCUCUGGGUACUGCCAGGGGCUCCCCGGAGGAAGAGCUGCCCCUGCCAGCCUUUGAGAAGCUGAACCCCUACCCAACCCCGUCUCCACCACACCCACUGUAUCCUGGCCGCAGGGUAAUAGAGUUCUCUGAGGAUAAGGUUCGGAUCCCCCGCAACAGCCCCCUGCCCAACUGCACUUACGCUACCCGCCAGGCCAUUUCCCUGAGCCUGGUAGAGGAGGGGAGUGAGCGGGCCCGCCCCAGCCCAGUGCCCAGCACCCCUGCCUCAGCCCAGGCCUCACCCCACCACCAGCCCAGCCCAGCACCCCUAACACUCAGUGCCCCAGCUAGCUCUGCCAGCUCUGAAGAGGACCUGCUGGUCAGCUGGCAGCGGGCAUUUGUGGACCGUACUCCACCACCUGCUGCUGUGGCCCAGCGCACAGCCUUUGGACGCGAUGCCCUCCCUGAGCUGCAGCGCCAUUUUGCCCAUAGCCCCGCUGACAGAGAUGAGGUGGUCCAGGCACCUUCUGCCCGACCCGAAGAGAGUGAGCUUUUGCUACCCACAGAACCUGACUCUGGCUUUCCCAGGGAGGAAGAAGAGCUGAACCUGCCUAUCAGUCCUGAGGAAGAGCGCCAGAGCCUGCUGCCCAUUAACAGGGGCACAGAGGAGGGGCCAGGCACUUCCCACACCGAGGGCAGGGCCUGGCCACUCCCCAGCUCCAGUCGCCCCCAGCGCAGCCCCAAGAGGAUGGGGGUUCACCACCUGCACCGCAAGGACAGCCUGACCCAGGCCCAGGAGCAGGGCAACCUGCUCAACUAGGGCCCCUGCUGGCCUUCCUGCCAUUGCUGCACCAGGACUGCAAGGAGUCCCCACACCUUGGCAGCUCAGGGUCCCCAGUCCAAGCCCUUGACCUCUCCUCUAUCCAGACCCGCACAGCUGUUUCCUGUGUGGAUGGGGUCAGGUUGUGGGCCAUGCCAGGCCUGUCAGCUGCGUUGACUGACUGCAGCAGCUUGCCUCAUGGUUUUCCCUUUUUCUUAGAAUAUUUAUUCUUCAGAGGUAACAUGCAGUUGGGUCUCAAGACCUUUCCUCCAAUCAGCCCAACCCAGCCCAGACUGGGCUUUUCUGGGGAGCUGAGGAGUUUAUCAGUAUUCAUCUUCCAUCCUUUCAUAGUCACAAGUUUUGUUAUUUUGUUUUUUUUUGGGGGUGAUGGUGUAAUUGUUAACCUCAUUUCCGUUUCCUACCUGUUUGCUUCCCCCCCCAGUCCUCCGCAUGAGCUGUUGCCCUCCAGGGGCCUGGCACAGCUGGCCUUGGGGACGAGGGAGAGGACUGAUUCAGGGCCCCCUCAGCUGUCUCCUCCCUCCCUCUGGAAAGGAGGGUGGGGCUCAGGGGCCUCAAGCUGGGCUCUGUGUGAGGCCUGGCCCCCACUCCCAACCUUGGCUCUAGACUGUUACUCUUAAGCUUUGAGAAAUUUUCACAUUGAUGACUAUUUUAAAAUCAAAUAAAACUAUUUUACUGGUA